AUGGCAUGGAGUGAGUCUUUGCCUCCCCUGUGCAAUCCUUCUUCCCCAACCUGCCAGCUUUCCUCUUAUCCUGACCACAGUUCACCACCAUCCCUUUUCCCCAAUCUCAGCUGCCUGGUCAGCACCUCUUUCGAACAUUCUGAGCCCCAACUUUGCAGUAAGGUGGUAGAAAAUGGAAAUCCAGAGAGCUGCAAAAAGAUUUUUUUUUAAUGUAAUGAAUGGGGAGUAGUUUUGUGAACACACUCGUAUUCACCUCUUCUUUCCUCUGGGAGGCCUGCCUGCCUUCCCCUCCCCCCCAACCUUGAUCCCUGUCUGCUGGAAAAGGCGCGAUUGCUUCUCUUCCUCUUCUGCCCAAGACCAAGACUCUAGGUCUGAUAUCCUUUUUAGCCACACACACACACCCCCCACACACGAAGUCUUCUUAAUCUUCUUGAAUUUACCAGUUACUCUGGACACUUCUUGCCAUAACCCCAUUUCACAGACAAAGGCUUAGGAGGGAAAAAGAACCAAACUGUUUCUGUGUUUGUCAUGUUAAUGAUGUCCAUCCCCACACACCCAGUUCCCAUCCCUGAUGCUUCUUGUGCCUGUAUCUUGAACCUUCAGAAUGAAAAAAAAAAAAAUCUCUUGGAUAGCUUGAUACAGUUUCUUUAGAAAUCUGCAUUGUUGCUUCUGGUUUAUGGCCAUGGAGAAAAUACCAGCCCCCACCCAAAAUGCACCGCAGCCAAGUCGGCUAAAGGCGAUGAGUGUUGGAGUCAGUAGGGGGCGCAUUCUCUGCACUGGGUAAGGCUGCAGAGGGGGGAAGGGCCCCCGAGCUAGAACAGGAUGUGCUUCACAGCGCCUUCUACAGACCAUGGGAAAAUGGGCCCAGCAAGACACACUCGCACUCUUAGUUGGUGAGCUGACAGCAACAUGGCGAAGGAUUAAGUGAGUCAAGAGCAGUGAUUUUACUUCUUUUAAAGAGCCCACCCUGCAUUUUAGAAGUUUUCUCCUUUUACUUUUUCAAAACUGUUGGCCCCCAGUCCAUAUUUGUUCUUGACGAAUCACCUUGGCACAUCCUUGGUUCGGAUUCCCUUCCUCUGGAGUUCUUCCACCUCAAGUUUUGAAUGUGUCACCAUAUCUUUCCUAAGUCUGGUGGUAAAGGAGAAGGUUUGAAACAAAGUAACAGGUUUGGGGGCAUAGCUGGUUAACUCCCUUCUUCAUAGGCCAAAUCUUUCCAAUUCUUUGAGAGUUAAAAAUCAUUCUUGAGAGAUGUUGGAUUAAGUGUGUAGAUGGGUGUCAUGAUUUGCAAAGCCUUGUUGGUAAACAUCAAGCCCAUGUUGGGUUCUUCAUUGUCGAACUCAAGUGUUGAUUGUAAAAAUUUCGUUUCCCUCCAAAUUUGGACUUGUAAUUGCCAUUCAUUAUCUCAGCAGCCAACCACCUUUACAAAAAUGUUGAUACCAGUCUUCUGUGAGCACCCACCUUCUUAGGGUGUGUUGAUUUCCAUAGAUUUUACUCCUCUUGUUAUUUCCAUAGGUGUGAGAUGCACAAUGCGAAACCUAGGCCCCAGCUUUUACACCAUGAUGCGCAGGGUUGUACUUUUUGUACUGAACUGAUAGGUGGCCUAGUGGUUAUGCCCUGUACUACCAUUUUGAGGAUCUGGACUCCGUUUCCUGCCUUGCUCUUUGGACCACAUUGUCAAUUCACACCGAAUACCGUAGCAGUAGGCAGGACAGUUCCAAUUCAACAAAAACCUCUUUACCCUGGCACUCAAAACUGUAAUGAUGAUGAACUGAAACUAUGUUCCAACUUCCUGUCAACAAUCUUGGCAGUUUAAGAAAAGCCCGGAAAACUGUGAAAAAAAUACUUAGUGACAUUGGGUUGGAAUACUGUAAAGAACAUAUAGAAGAUUUUAAACAAUUUGAACCUAAUGACUUUUAUUUGAAAAACACUACAUGGGAGGAUGUAGGACUGUGGGACCCAUCACUUACGAAAAACCAGGACUAUCGGACAAAACCUUUCUGCUGCAGCGCUUGUCCAUUUUCCUCAAAAUUCUUCUCUGCCUACAAAAGUCAUUUCCGCAAUGUCCAUAGUGAAGACUUUGAAAAUAGGAUUCUCCUUAAUUGCCCCUACUGUACCUUCAAUGCAGACAAAAAGACUUUGGAAACACACAUUAAAAUAUUUCAUGCUCCGAACGCCAGCGCACCAAGUAGCAGCCUCAGCACUUUCAAAGAUAAAAACAAAAAUGAUGGCCUUAAACCUAAGCAGGCUGACAGUGUAGAGCAAGCUGUUUAUUACUGUAAGAAGUGCACUUACCGAGAUCCUCUUUAUGAAAUAGUUAGGAAGCACAUUUACAGGGAACAUUUUCAGCAUGUGGCAGCACCUUACAUAGCAAAGGCAGGAGAAAAAUCACUCAAUGGGGCAGUCCCCUUAGGCUCGAAUGCCCGAGAAGAGAGUAGUAUUCACUGCAAGCGAUGCCUUUUCAUGCCAAAGUCCUAUGAAGCUUUGGUACAGCAUGUCAUCGAAGACCAUGAACGUAUAGGCUAUCAGGUCACUGCCAUGAUUGGGCACACAAAUGUAGUGGUUCCCCGAUCCAAACCCUUGAUGCUAAUUGCUCCCAAACCUCAAGACAAGAAGAGCAUGGGACUCCCACCAAGGAUCGGUUCCCUUGCUUCUGGAAAUGUCCGGUCUUUACCAUCACAGCAGAUGGUGAAUCGACUCUCAAUACCAAAGCCUAACUUAAAUUCUACAGGAGUCAACAUGAUGUCCAGUGUUCAUCUGCAGCAGAACAACUAUGGAGUCAAAUCUGUAGGCCAGGGUUACAGUGUUGGUCAGUCAAUGAGACUGGGUCUAGGUGGCAACGCACCAGUUUCCAUUCCUCAACAAUCUCAGUCUGUAAAGCAGUUACUUCCAAGUGGAAACGGAAGGUCUUAUGGGCUUGGGUCAGAGCAGAGGUCCCAGGCACCAGCAAGAUACUCCCUGCAGUCUGCUAAUGCCUCUUCUCUCUCAUCGGGCCAGUUAAAGUCUCCUUCCCUCUCUCAGUCACAGGCAUCCAGAGUGUUAGGUCAGUCCAGUUCCAAACCUGCUGCAGCUGCCACAGGCCCUCCCCCAGGUAACACUUCCUCAACUCAAAAGUGGAAAAUAUGUACAAUCUGUAAUGAGCUUUUUCCUGAAAAUGUCUAUAGUGUGCACUUCGAAAAAGAACAUAAAGCUGAGAAAGUCCCAGCAGUAGCCAACUACAUUAUGAAAAUACACAAUUUUACUAGCAAAUGCCUCUACUGUAAUCGCUAUUUACCCACAGAUACUCUGCUCAACCAUAUGUUAAUUCAUGGUCUGUCUUGUCCAUAUUGCCGUUCAACUUUCAAUGAUGUGGAAAAGAUGGCCGCACACAUGCGGAUGGUUCACAUUGAUGAAGAGAUGGGACCUAAAACAGAUUCUACUUUGAGUUUUGAUUUGACAUUGCAGCAGGGUAGUCACACUAACAUCCAUCUCCUGGUAACUACAUACAAUCUGAGGGAUGCCCCAGCUGAAUCUGUUGCUUACCAUGCCCAAAAUAAUCCUCCAGUUCCUCCAAAGCCACAGCCAAAGGUUCAGGAAAAGGCAGAUAUCCCUGUAAAAAGUUCACCUCAAGCUGCAGUGCCCUAUAAAAAAGAUGUUGGGAAAACCCUUUGUCCUCUUUGCUUUUCAAUCCUAAAAGGACCCAUAUCUGAUGCACUUGCACAUCACUUACGAGAGAGGCACCAAGUUAUUCAGACGGUUCAUCCAGUUGAGAAAAAGCUCACCUACAAAUGUAUCCAUUGCCUUGGUGUGUAUACCAGCAACAUGACCGCCUCAACUAUCACUCUGCAUCUAGUUCACUGCAGGGGCGUUGGAAAGACCCAAAAUGGCCAGGAUAAGACAAAUGCACCCUCUCGGCUUAAUCAGUCUCCAAGUCUGGCACCUGUGAAGCGCACUUACGAGCAAAUGGAAUUUCCCUUACUGAAAAAACGAAAGUUAGAUGAUGAUAGUGAUUCACCCAGCUUCUUUGAAGAGAAGCCUGAAGAGCCUGUUGUUUUAGCUUUAGACCCCAAGGGUCAUGAAGAUGAUUCCUAUGAAGCCAGGAAAAGCUUUCUAACAAAGUAUUUCAACAAACAGCCCUAUCCCACCAGGAGAGAAAUUGAGAAGCUAGCAGCCAGUUUAUGGUUAUGGAAGAGUGACAUCGCUUCCCAUUUUAGUAACAAAAGGAAGAAGUGUGUCCGUGAUUGUGAAAAGUACAAGCCUGGCGUGUUGCUGGGGUUUAACAUGAAAGAAUUAAAUAAAGUCAAGCAUGAGAUGGAUUUUGAUGCUGAGUGGCUAUUUGAAAAUCAUGAUGAGAAGGAUUCCAGAGUCAAUGCUAGUAAGACUGCUGACAAAAAGCUCAACCUUGGGAAGGAAGAUGACAGUUCCUCAGACAGUUUUGAAAAUUUGGAAGAAGAAUCCAAUGAAAGUGGUAGCCCUUUUGACCCUGUUUUUGAAGUUGAACCUAAAAUCUCUAACGAUAACCCAGAGGAACAUGUACUGAAGGUAAUUCCUGAGGAUGCUUCAGAAUCUGAGGAGAAGCUAGACCAAAAAGAGGAUGGUUCAAAAUACGAAACUAUUCAUUUGACUGAGGAACCAACCAAACUAAUGCACAAUGCAUCUGAUAGUGAGGUUGACCAAGACGAUGUUGUUGAGUGGAAAGACGGUGCUUCUCCAUCUGAGAGUGGGCCUGGAUCCCAACAAGUGUCAGACUUUGAGGACAAUACCUGCGAAAUGAAACCAGGAACCUGGUCUGACGAGUCUUCCCAAAGCGAAGAUGCAAGGAGCAGUAAGCCAGCUGCCAAAAAAAAGGCUACCAUGCAAGGUGACAGAGAGCAGUUGAAAUGGAAGAAUAGUUCCUAUGGAAAAGUUGAAGGGUUUUGGUCUAAGGACCAGUCACAGUGGAAGAAUGCAUCUGAGAAUGAUGAGCGCUUAUCUAACCCCCAGAUUGAGUGGCAGAAUAGCACAAUUGACAGUGAGGAUGGGGAACAGUUUGACAACAUGACUGAUGGAGUAGCUGAGCCCAUGCAUGGCAGCUUAGCCGGAGUUAAACUGAGCAGCCAACAGGCCUAAGUGCCAGGUUCCCUGGCGUUGGUGACAUGCUGCAGCCUGGAACUCUGAUAUCCAGUGUGACUGCAAAGCUGUCUUCUCACUGGUACUGCCUUGUGAGUACUGGUUGGACUGUGGGGCAUGUGGCCGCUGCAGUUCCAGUGGUUAUUUCUAAGUCUAUGACAGGACAGGCUGUUCUUGCUUCAGAACCUUCUCUGACAGACACGGUAACUAAAUGUGAAAAACCAAUAAGCUGGUGACUCAUGAAUACACACGAGGAAAAGCAGAGGUUUAUUUUAUCUGCCUUUUCAACAUUUCUUUCCCUCUGUGAAAUGAUUGGUCAGAUGUCUUUGAGAAGUGUUAAACUAAUUCACAUGGUAGUGUAGGGCCAACAUACAAGCUACCAGUCUAAUGUGUAUAGUAGACUUUGGGAAAAGCGAUUUUUUUUCAUGUAUUCAUUCUGAAUAGUUGAAAUGUAUAUUUGUACAGUCUUUUAGACCUAUUCAAGUGAUGCUCAUGAUCCUGUUACUGUGUGCCCAUCAUAGAUUUCUUUUUUUAGUGUUGCCCUUGCUGUGUAAUAAACGCUCUAUCUAGUUUACCUAGCAAAAGCUCAAAACUGCGCUAGUAUGGACUUUUUGGACAGACUUAGUUUUUGCACAUAACCUUGUACAAUCUUGCAACAGAGGCCAGCCACGUAAGAUAUAUAUCUGGACUCUCUUGUAUUAUAGGAUUUUUCUUGUUCUGAAUAUCCUUGACAUUACAGCUGUCAAAAACAAAAACUGGUAUUUCAGAUCUGUUUUCUGAAAUCUUUUAAGCUAAAAUCACAUGCAAGAAUUGACUUUGCAGCUACUAAUUUUGACACCUUUUAGAUCUGUAUAAAAGUGUGUUGUGUUGAAGCAGCAAACCAAUGAGUGCUGCAUUUUGGAUAUUUAGUUUUAUCUUUAGUUCAACACCAUCAUGGUGGAUUCAUUUAUACCAUCUAAUAUAUGACACACUGUUGUAGUAUGUAUAAUUUUGUGAUCUUUAUUUUCCCUUUGUAUUCAUUUUAAGCAUCUAAAUAAAUUGCUGUAUUGUGCUUAAUGUAAAUAUUUGCUUUAUUACACAUGACAGUCCUGUGUGUCCAUUAUAUCUUUUGCCAUUUAAUGCCAUAACUCUUUCAUCAGAGAUGGCAGCCACAGUCACAGAGGAAACUUGUGGAAAACCCAAGAUCUGUCAUCUGCAAAUAGAAUGCUUUCUCUUGAGGCACCUGGUACAAAAUCUGUUUUUCUUUUUUUUUUUUUUUUUUUUUUUUUUUUUUAACUGAAAAACAAACACCCUUGAGUUUUUCAGUUCACCUUUUGUUAAGGAGCAGAGCCUGCAUAUAUAUGUAAAUGUCUCAAUGAUAAAAAAAAAAAUGUAAACAUGGAUUGGCAUUAAUUUGCAAGCAGAAUCUUAAUAGCCUGAUGGGUUUUUUGUUUGUUUUUUCUUCUAGAUGAAGUUAAACGUUCGUUUUCACCUUACGAUGGGAACAACUGUAGUGCAGGCGGCUCUGCCUCUAUUUGCCACUCUUGGCCCUCUUGCUAUUAAGGGAAAGGCUUUGAAGAGCACAGCACUGACAGGGCUGUAAAGAUGGAAGGAGCUGGUAUUUUUACCAUGCGUAGAUUCCCAAGAGAACUUGUACUAAAAAGCAGAAAGUUACAAGGAAGCAGAAUUAGGCCAACAUUUCCAGCAAUUAAAACAAUGAUGGGAAACUCCAAUCCAUGAGGAGGCUGGUCAGUCACCUCAAGGAUAGUGGCCUAAAGAAGUCUGAAGUGGCUGAUGUCCAUAACUUCUGAGUCUGUUUCCAAAAGAAAGACUCUUGUUAAUGCUGUUACCAGAGAGUAGAGAUUUGACCAGCCUCUCCCUAAAAUGUAAGCUUCUCAACAACAGUACAGGAAGAAGUGCAAGAGUAGACUAGAACCUUUAAGGAAUUUGGGGCUGGAACGGAGCUAUGUUGCAUCUGUUGUUAUACAGGUAGAUUAUAAGUUCUACAUGCACCAGCCAAAACUUAGGACAGGAUGUCCCCAAAUUAAGAUACUACAGAUUACCAAAUCAGAAAUAACCAGCUGGAUUUAGGCCAGCUCACAUUUAUUUGGAAAUUACCCUCCCUGAUUAACAGGCUUCUGAGUUGUACGUGGAGGACUAAUGAGACUUGUACAAGACACCACGGGGCUUGGGGUCCAGGUCCCAGUUGGAUAUCGGAACAGACACAGAUAAGUGUGUUUCCUCAUUAAGGUGGUGAGAGUGUGCCUUUUGGCAUUCAGAAAAGGGUUUAGCCACCCUAAGAGUUGGAAAUAAAGAUUCCCAACUGGAAAUGUUGCAGAAUCCCUACAAGUGUCUCAAUAAAAGCCAUUUUAAAAGAAUAUUGUUGCUACUGUUUGCUUUUCAAAUAAUCUGGAGAUCGUUGGCUAUGGCAACGUGCUGCCACCUAAUUAGAGAAUGCCUGUAAAUGUAGGCUGAACACUUCUAACAUGAGAAAACCUAAGUAUCCUA